AAUGCUUACAGCUGAGAAGCAGGUCAGUCAGGUUCCUGGGCGCUCUGUUACACAAGCAAGAUACAGCCAGCCCCACCUAAUUUUGUUUCCCUGGCACCCUCCUGCUCAGUGCGACAUUGUCACACUUAACCCAUCUGUUUUCUCUAAUGCACGACAGAUUCCUUUCAGACAGGACAACUGUGAUAUUUCAGUUCCUGAUUGUAAAUACCUCCUAAGCCUGAAGCUUCUGUUACUAGCCAUUGUGAGCUUCAGUUUCUUCAUCUGCAAAAUGGGCAUAAUACAAUCUAUUCUUGCCACAUCAAGGGAUUGUUAUUCCUUUAAAAAAAAACCAAUACCAAAGAAGCCUACAAUGUUGGCCUUAGCCAAAAUUCUGUUGAUUUCAACGUUGUUUUAUUCACUUCUAUCGGGGAGCCAUGGAAAAGAAAAUCAAGACAUAAACACAACACAGAACAUUGCAGAAGUUUUUAAAACAAUGGAAAAUAAACCUAUUUCUUUGGAAAGUGAAGCAAACUUAAACUCAGAUAAAGAAAAUAUAACCACCUCAAAUCUCAAGGCGAGUCAUUCCCCUCCUUUGAAUCUACCCAACAACAGCCACGGAAUAACAGAUUUCUCCAGUAACUCAUCAGCAGAGCAUUCUUUGGGCAGUCUAAAACCCACAUCUACCAUUUCCACAAGCCCUCCCUUGAUCCAUAGCUUUGUUUCUAAAGUGCCUUGGAAUGCACCUAUAGCAGAUGAAGAUCUUUUGCCCAUCUCAGCACAUCCCAAUGCUACACCUGCUCUGUCUUCAGAAAACUUCACUUGGUCUUUGGUCAAUGACACCGUGAAAACUCCUGAUAACAGUUCCAUUACAGUUAGCAUCCUCUCUUCAGAACCAACUUCUCCAUCUGUGACCCCCUUGAUAGUGGAACCAAGUGGAUGGCUUACCACAAACAGUGAUAGCUUCACUGGGUUUACCCCUUAUCAAGAAAAAACAACUCUACAGCCUACCUUAAAAUUCACCAAUAAUUCAAAACUCUUUCCAAAUACGUCAGAUCCCCAAAAAGAAAAUAGAAAUACAGGAAUAGUAUUCGGGGCCAUUUUAGGUGCUAUUCUGGGUGUCUCAUUGCUUACUCUUGUGGGCUACUUGUUGUGUGGAAAAAGGAAAACGGAUUCAUUUUCCCAUCGGCGACUUUAUGACGACAGAAAUGAACCAGUUCUGCGAUUAGACAAUGCACCGGAACCUUAUGAUGUGAGUUUUGGGAAUUCUAGCUACUACAAUCCAACUUUGAAUGAUUCAGCCAUGCCAGAAAGUGAAGAAAAUGCACGUGAUGGCAUUCCUAUGGAUGACAUACCUCCACUUCGUACUUCUGUAUAGAACUAACAGCAAAAAGGCGUUAAACAGCAAGUGUCAUCUACAUCCUAGCCUUUUGACAAAUUCAUCUUUCAAAAGGUUACACAAAAUUACUGUCACGUGGAUUUUGUCAAGGAGAAUCAUAAAAGCAGGAGACCAGUAGCAGAAAUGUAGACAGGAUGUAUCAUCCAAAGGUUUUCUUUCUUACAAUUUUUGGCCAUCCUGAGGCAUUUACUAAGUAGCCUUAAUUUGUAUUUUAGUAGUAUUUUCUUAGUAGAAAAUAUUUGUGGAAUCAGAUAAAACUAAAAGAUUUCACCAUUACAGCCCUGCCUCAUAACUAAAUAAUAAAAAUUAUUCCACCAAAAAAUUCUAAAACAAUGAAGAUGACUCUUUACUGCUCUGCCUGAAGCCCUAGUACCAUAAUUCAAGAUUGCAUUUUCUUAAAUGAAAAUUGAAAGGGUGCUUUUUAAAGAAAAUUUGACUUAAAGCUAAAAAGAGGACAUAGCCCAGAGUUUCUGUUAUUGGGAAAUUGAGGCAAUAGAAAUGACAGACCUGUAUUCUAGUACGUUAUAAUUUUCUAGAUCAGCACACACAUGAUCAGCCCACUGAGUUAUGAAGCUGACAAUGACUGCAUUCAACGGGGCCAUGGCAGGAAAGCUGACCCUACCCAGGAAAGUAAUAGCUUCUUUAAAAGUCUUCAAAGGUUUUGGGAAUUUUAACUUGUCUUAAUAUAUCUUAGGCUUCAAUUAUUUGGGUGCCUUAAAAACUCAAUGAGAAUCAUGGUAAAAAAAAAAAGUUAACCAAAGAAUAUACCUGUACAUAAUUUGUACAGUUUUAAGUUGUUAGAUAGGAACUGGAUUUCUUAUGUAUUAGACAUUAUUGCUCAAUCAUAAUGGAAUAGAUUCUGCAUCCCUAAAUGUAUGAACCAUAAGGUUAAAAAAGAUGAAUGGAAAUAUCAAACAACUUUUUACUGAGCAUCAGUUUCAUAAUCAAUAAUAUAAGAAGAUUAAUUUGGAUUCUAGUAUGUUUCAGUUUGUUUUUAAUUACCACCUUCCUUUGGUAGAAAAAAUAUGUUCCUUGAUGUAGGAAAGUCUAGGUUUUAGAGAUUAGAGGAUGAGAUCAAGAGUUAAAUUCCUAAAGAAGCACUGAAUAUAUGAAGAGAGCAAACAAAUCAAGUACCAACCUAGAGGCUUUAUUUUUGAAUUGAUUCAUGGUGUGUGUGUGUGUGUGUGUGUGUGUGUGUGUGUGUGUGUAACACAGAAACAGCUUCAGAAAAUAAGGGAUAGAAAGUAAUGAAGAAAGUACUUACCCCAUAUUGCCAUAAAAAUAGCAAAGAAGACUGUCCCUCCAUUAUCGAACAAAUAUGUCACCUGAGUAGAAAACAAACAGAAAUAUUAGUCAUGCAAAUUGAUUAUAAUAAGCCAGUGAAUACUGUUUGCACUCAGGUACUAUGAUUUUUUCUCAAAUAGAAUCAUAUUAUUUUAUAGUACAGAAAUAUUAUAUAUGAAUUCCUUUCAUGGGUCUUGCAACAAUUUCACAUGAUUUUUCUCAUGGGGAGAGGUGAAGAAACAACAUUAGCCCUCUUCUCUCCUCUCUUGAUUCCCUUUAUACCCCACCAUCAUUUCUGAUUAUAAAUAAUUCUACCAUUCUAUGGAAGUAUUUGUGGGUCACAGAUUGUCAAACUACUUAAUGAAAGUUGUAUGAAAUUAGUUUUUCAGGUGAGGCAUUCCUAGUUGCAAUUCCUGUUAGCAAAACUUCUAGGAGUGGGGAAGUUGGAAAAUGCAGGAUUCUUCCAGUGAGCCAGCAUUUCCCAUAGCUAACCCUAUUCUCUUAGUCUUUCAAAAUGUAGAAUGGGUCCAAUAAUGGCUAUAAGAUGUAAUAAAUCCCAUCUUAAUUUGUUUUAAAAGUUUCAUAAAUCACUGAACACUUAUGAAACAAAGUGUUUUUUAAUCAGAUAUCAACUGAAACUUCAUAAAGGAUGCAUAGUUUUAUAAUGUUAUUGAAUCAAAUUUUAAGGCUUGUAUUGUUUGAUUUUAAUAAAGUAUAAAUUCAAUUUA